CAUUCAUUUAUAAUAAAAAAUGAUACAACUGUGUUGUAGCAGUAGGCCUCCGGAUGGAUGCAAAUUUGUCUACAAUUUUUUUUUUUAGUCAACGUAAUCACCAGCAGGGUAGGAGACAUUCACAUUCUGGAGCUGACGGGAAGGGAUAUUAAGAAAAAGAGCCAAGCCGACUGACCCACUCAGGACCUCAUUAAUACUAGACAUCUUUAUCUGUGUUUAACUAUAAUUUAUUCUCCAGAGAAAAAGUGAGAAGAAAACCCAAGUAUUCUUUUGGGUUAUUACUUCAUGUAGGGCCUCCCUCGAGCAUUAUUUUUAACUCAAAAAUAGAUUUUUGGCAACCAUGUUGUUAUAAUAAUAAUAGAGCAAACAGUAAAAAACAAAAAUGUCACAUCAAGAUUUUUAGAAGAAGGCUGCCUUAUUACUUUGAGUUACUCCUACGUGUUUGUAAUCCUUAUAUUAUAAACUGUUGGCUGCUGAUUUUUUGUUUUGUCCUGUCAGCCAGAGUCUGACAUGAUGACAUAUGACUGGCAGAGUUGUGUUCCUUGUAGAGCAGGGGAGCAGAAGGCCAUUCCGUGGUUAAGACAAUGAGGAGAUUAACAAAUUGGCUUUUAAAUCAAAAUGCCAUUUUGUGUAGAAUUUGUAUUUUGUUUGUCAAAAAUACUUGUUUUCCAUUCCUAGGAAAAAAUCAAUCAAUCAAGCAAAUUAAUUCAACACACCCUUUAUGAGCUUGAUACAACCUACAAACAUAGAUACAACCUAGAGUACAUAGUGUGAGAUUAAUGUAUUCAUUGAUUCAUUUAUUCAUUCAUUCAUUCAAAAAUAUAUAUUAAAUAUCUAGCGUGUGCCAGACACUGUUUAUGACAUUGGGGUAAAGCAAAGACCAUACGUUGUAGUCCAGUAGAGGAAAGUAGAUAAUAAGCAACCAAAAAUAUACAUAUAUAAUAUGUUAGUUGGUGAUAGUGCUUGAAAGAAGUAAAAAGUUUAGUAAGGGGGUGGAAAAGGAUGGGUAGUGAUGCCACUUAUUGUUCAGUAGGAGUCUCCAAGGGCCAUGAAACAGUGAAAGAGCAUAUUUUUCUGGAGUGAUACCAAUUUUGGAAAAAUUCUAUGGACUACUAAUGUGCACUAUCUGAAGGACUGUAAUCUUAUAGAAAAGGAUCUUAUGACUCAGGUCUAUGAUAAACAAUUUUUCAAAGUAAAUUACUUUUGAGAGUGGGCUAUAAAAUGGUUUUAAAAUCAAAUCUAAUCAGUGUUGGACAGGGACACUAUAAGAAAAGAUAAAUACAUAAUACUCUUUCUCGUAACAUAAAUAUAAAAAAUCUUACAAAAUAGAACAUAAUGAUCAAGUUGGGUUUAUUCCAAUCAUGGAAGAUUAAAAAGCAAUAUAACUUACCACAUUUACAAAAUAAAAGAAGAAAUGAAUGUUUUUCUAAGUAAAUACAGAAAAGAAAUUUGAAUUUAACAUUUUCGAUAAUUUAAAAACACUCAAACUUGUAAUAAAAAUGAAUUUUUCCAACUUGACAAAGUGUGUCUGACAUCAUAUUUAAUUAUGAAAUACUUGGCCAGGCGCGGUGGCUCACACCUCUAAUCCCAGCACUUUGGGAGGCUGAGGAGGGCAGAUCACCUGAGGUCAGGCGUUCAAGACCAGCCUGACUAACAUGGUGAAGCCCCAUCUGUACUAAGAAUACAAAAAUUAGCCGGGCAUUGUGGCACAUGCCUGAGUCCCAGCUACUUGACAGGCUGAGGCAGUAGAAUAGCUUGAACCUGGGAGGCGGAGGUUGCAGUGAGCCGAGAUUGUGCCACUGCACUCCAGCCUGCACAACAGAAUGAGACUCCAUCUCAAAUAAUAAUAAUCAUCAUAAUGAAAUACUUAAAACUUACUCCAUAAAAUCAGGCAUAAGGCAAGAAUACCAUUGUAGCCACUUAUAUCCAAUAUUGUACUGGACCAUGUAUUUACUGAAUAAAAUAAAAGGACACAAAUAUCAAGGGAUUAGAAAAAUAACAUGGUUGUGUAUGAAGGUGCAAGGACCUCCUGUGACGCUAUUCCUGAAUAGUCUGAAACACUCAUUCUACAAUAACAGAAUUGUAGCAAUCAAAUAUGUAAGGUGAGCUAUGUAGUGGUAUUCUGAGAAGCAGCAUGGUGUGGUGGUUAAAAUUAUGGACUCUGGAGCCAGGCUGCUAGAGUGUAAAAACCCUAUGCCACCUCUUGCUAGCUAAGUAGCUUUGGGAAUCUUACUUAUUAAUCUGUGCCUCAGUUUCUCAUCUGUGAAAUGGGAAUAACAUUAUCUGCUUUAUGGGAUUAUUAUGAGGAUUAAAUAAAUGAAUGCUUGUAAAACACUUAGAAUAGUGCCUGACACAUAAGUGGUAUGCAUUCAUUUAGUAAAUAAUGACUUGGAAAAACAAAAUUUGGACUAUGAAAUUUUGAAAUUUUAAGUUGAAAAUUAAAAUGGUUUUAUUCACUUAUAUUGUCUGUCCAAAUAAUCAGUAUCACAUGGUUACACUUAAGUAGUACAUGUUAACAAAUGUGCCCAUGGUAAGAAUACAUUCUAAAUCUUAAUAAAAUGCAUCUUAAAUCACUAGUAAUAGUACUGAAAAUGUGACCUACCAAAUACUUAUGAUUGUAAAGUAAAAGUUAAAACUAGUAUUAUAUAAACAACUUUGAUAAUAUACUGUUGAAUGAUAAUUGUCAUCCUGGAAACAUGAAACUACACUGGAAAGCGGUUUCUAAUUAUCAUUCAUGUCUUUAGGUAUAACAUGUGAUUUAAUUAAUACAUACAAUCAUUACAAAAUCAUGACAGAUAAGAAAAAACUAUGGUCAGCAUUAAAAAGUGACUAGCCUAUUAUGUCAGAUGUUAUGCAGAUUGUCAGAUAUUAUGUUUACUUAUUAAUAGCAAAUUGUAUAAAUUUUUUAGGACCUGAAAGACUGUCUUUCCCACAAUGUUGAUUCUCAAGAAUGGAAUCGUAAUUUUUUUUCUUGAACACUCAUUUUGUCUCCAUUCAAUAAUAAACUCUCAUCACAAUAUCCUUCCUCUGAAUCCUCAUCCUGAUAUAUAUCUGUGAGUUCUAGUACCAAGGGCUCAGCAGUGCAUCUCACCAGCUUCAAACCCCAUGUCUCUAUUUGAUUUCUGCUAUACCCAUAGGGUGUGUGUUUGAUGCCAUUAAUUUAAUAAUAUCAAGAAGGUCCACUAAGUUCACUGGCAUAAGCAUUCCCAAGAAUGGUCCCAGUAAUCAUUUUCUACUGUCAGAUCAUUCCAGAAAACACUAAAAAUCUGUUAACUCAUUUUCCUGGGUUUAGCAAUUAAAAUUUAAGUAGAAAUAGUAGUUUUUAUAUUUUAGUCUUCCUUUUCUUGAAUUAGGAAAUAGAUUUUAGUCUUGGCAUUCUAACUUUAAAUUUUAAAUAAUACAAAACAUAUUGUAAUCCAGUGCAAUUUAUUGGAAUACUGUAAAGAAUUGGAUUUUAAAUAAUAGUGUAUGGAGUGCUGUGAGGUUAUUUUAAUAAUUAUAUGGUAGUCCUGUAUGUUUUUUUCAAAAUGUUGAUGUCUAGAUUAUAUUUAGAAACAGAAGGAUCUUUCCUGAAGCAGAAGGAGGGCCUGGGACUCAUGGUUAUGAUUUGAGAUUGUCCCACCCCCAUAAUCUCCACUGCUCACUGCAUAGUAUGCUCAUGAUCCAUUCACUCUGUUUAAAAUGUUACAAUAUUAGUUAAGAUUGGGUUCAUCUUUUAGUUUUACUUUGAGAGAUAUAGCAAACCAGUUUCUGAGAGCUGAUUUCUAUUUAAAGAACUGUGCAAAGCACUGAGGAAAUGUAAAAUUAAAAAUAAAAUAUACACCUACUUUUCCACAUACCUUGAUCAAUUUCAUAUAGCUAUUAUAGGGGCACAUUCAGAGCUGCUGCUCUAAGGAUUCCUUAUUCCACAAAGAAAACAGUUUCCGUGGGUUUUGGCAGCCUAAUAUUUUGUUAUGCUUUAUACAGGUAGGAAGGAGACUAGGCUGAUUGAAGAGAUUCAUUAUAAUAUAGUUUCAGCUCCUUCAUCCUGUCUGAUGGGGAAAAGUGAAGAAGAAUCUGCUAAAAAUAGAUAAGCAGAAUGCUGGAUCAACAAAAUAAGGAGACCUUUUCUUCUUUAGGUUUGUUUCCUAAAAAGGCCUGUGGGAACUCUUAUUUCUAAACAAGACCCGUGAAUUAAUUAGCAGAUAGUAAAAAUACGUGCAUUUCAAAAAUAAAAAUCGACACUUGAUUCAUUUGUACCACAUAAAAAGAGCUAAGACUUGGUGGGAAGAAGCAUUCUUACACGCAAGCUAUCCUUUCACAGGCAGAACAGUUUUAUCCUUUCAAAGUUAGCUGAAAAGGAAAAAAAAAUCUAUAUACCAAACCCCAUCUUCUAAAUUACCCCCAUUGAAAAUGAAAGAUGGGUUUUGGAGUUGAAGAUUUCAGAGAGCAGAUGUAGAAACUGAGAUUUUGGCAGCUUCUAUCAGAAACUAAUGAGCUUUGGGGAAACCCAGCUGAUGCAGAGUUUGGUAGAUUACUAUAAAAGCUACAGGGUGUCUAACACCUGUAGUGAACCAGCUUCAAGAUGGAACAUGGAAACUGACCAGAGGUAGCCUUUCCAAAUUACUUAUAAGAUUAUUCAACAGUAUAAAAAAAAUGAAAACACUGCCUAAUGUAAUAUUAUUCAAUAUAUCUAAACUUUACCUUCCUAUUAAUAAAUACACCACAUAUGCAUAUUCCUUUAAAGUAGGAGUGAUGAUACCUUAAAUUCUUGGUGGGUGGCUUACAUGGUCCAUUAGUCACCAUAAUACUAUGGCUGGGCUUUUUUUAGUGGUUGCUACCUAAGACAAUCAGUGGAUAAUACAAUGGCUCUCAGUGAGAGGCCUGGGGCCUUUGGCCAGGUGGUAGGAGAGCAGAGGGAUAGUGUGAAACACUGUAGUAGAAGAAAGUGCUGGCAGACCACAAAAGCUCACAUUUCUUAUACUCUGUAGUAAGGAACUUCCUUUCUGUGGCUGGUUCCUCUUACAGUUUUGCAGUUUACUUUCUUGCCAUGAAUGGUAAUAUACUAAGCAGCUAAUUUCAGUGUGUUCAUCCUAAAUAUAAUUAGUACAUGUUUGGCUCUUCAGGAAUCUGCACAUCUGACUGUAGGUUUUACAGGGAUAUACAAAUUAGACAAUCGUUAUGUGUUGAUGCUGGUAAGAUGCCGUUAUGGGACUUGAAGUCAAUAUUCAUACACAUGUAUUUUUCAGUUGCUCAGUCCUGCUGUAUCAAUAUGUGUGUUUGGAAGGGUAUGAAUAAAAGUGGAGGUGGGGGCUAUUAACAAGAAUGGACAGAAAUACCUGUGCCAAAGAUUGUGGCCCCCAAGUGUAUUAGACCUUUCCAAACCAUCUCAGCAUCCUACCAACACCUUCCCAAUUCAUAGGUCUAAUUCAGUGUUUCCCAUAAACUCUAAUCUCACUGUGGGCACUACCCCUUGAGUCCAGUGGAUCCAUCUUGGUAGCUCUUAGCCUGUAGAACCUCUAAUUACUUACCAUUAAAUUUUAGCAUAAAGUUCAAGUCUCUAAUCACAACCUAAAAUAUUCUAUACAAGUUCAUCUCGUCUACCAAAUUGUCACUGUUGUCUGGAAAACAUUCAGGUAUCCUUUCUCUUCUCUGAAUGUUCCGUGCUCUUCCUUUGUCAGAGUCUUUGCCUCAUCCUUUCCUCCGCUUGCUGUGCUCUUCCUCAUUCUUCAUUUUUGUAAUUGAAGUAUAGUCUUUAUUUGGCAGUAUCUAAGGAGCAGAGCUGUCAGAUGUUAAGUGAAACAUGGUGAAAAAUGGCAACUGCAGUGAUAUCAGUAUUUCCAUUUGUUUGGAUUUCUUUAUGACAAAUUAUCAUAUACAUGUGGGAGAAGUCUAAACGUCCUUCUGAUUUUUUUGUGAAAAAGUGAAGGAAUGUUAAGUCAUUUUCCAUGUGGCACAUUAAAGCUGCCAAAAACAAAUCUAGCCUGAAUUUGGGUACUUAAUUAUAUAAUUAAGAAAUCUGUAUCGGGCACAUUUUGUAUUCAGAAAUCUGCAGUGAUUUCCACUUAGGACCUUAACAGUGUGUUUGCAGAGAUUAGUGAUUCCCAAGUUCAAAUCUUGUGAACUCAUCUCUUAAUCCAUAAAUACUUAUUGGACAACUACUACAUGUAAGUCUUUCUAAAAGUGAGCAUGUCAAAUUUCUAGUUAUCGUGUAAACAUGUCCUGAGAGAAUAGAAGCAUUAGAAUCAACCUGGGAAGAUAUUUUACUCUCUUACAAGGGUUACUUAAGAAUGUAUAGUGUGCCCAUCACUGUGCUAGGCAACAAACUUUGUUGUUCCUUGAGAAUUAAGAGUUCCUGAUCUCAGAAAGGUCACUUUCUGGCAGAAAAAGUCUUAAAAUUUAAUUUCAGUGUAUUCUCAUAAAUACAAUAAAGUAAACAUGUUAACGAUACAAAAUAAUUAAUGGUGAGAGAGGUGACAGUGGAUCAUUAGGAAGGUUUUCCUGAAGUGCCUGAGUUUUGAAAAAAGAAAUAACUCAUAUUAUCAUCAUAGAGUGUUCCCAGACUCCCCCUGCCACCUGGAGCCAAGGUUCUUUUCUUAGUUUCUUUCUCUCCAUUGCCUUGCUAGAAAGGGGCUGCCUUUGGCUGAUCAGUUUUUUGAUUAUCACAAUCAAGAGAUGGAAGAAGGUGACCACAUGAGUGAACCAAGGCUGGGAAAGGAGUUUGGGGUUAAUUUAGGAGGACAAAUAGGGGAUGCUAUUGUCUAUCAGAAGAAUAAACAGGAGAGAAAGGUACAGACUUUAAAAAGUGUAGCUCUUCUACAUGAUGUAUCACAUUUAUUGCUUCAAGAACUUAAAUGUCGUAGAGUAGCGUAGAGACACGUGAAGUAAUAAAUGUUCCACCCAUUAUUUUCAGAUCUGGGAGUGAACCAUAUGGGACACAGAAGGGUAAGUGGAUAUUUACUGGGAAGAUGAAAGUGACAUCCAACCAGAGAAAUCAGAAUGGCAGAGGCAUAAAUACAUGAAAUAGCAUGGGCUUUUAAGCUGACUCUAAGAAAGUUAGUAUUGACAGCUGUACAGAGGGAAGGGAAAUGUAAUGGCAUGGACAUGUCAGUAGAUGCAGCUGUGUCUAUAGGAUACGCCAUCUUAAUAUGGAUAAUUUCUAAUCAGUCUAAUGGUUCAUAAUUUUAACAGCUGUUUGACUGACUCUUAGCAUAAAUUGCCACACUACCAGCUAAUUGACUUGACGUCUGGUGACAGAGUCUUAAUUGCUUGUAAAGAAAUGAUGAUUGGAUAUUAGGCUGAAUUGAUCCAUUUAGCACAUUUACAAUCUUUUGGUAUUGUCAUCUAUCCUUUCCCUUGUGUUUUACCUUCUAUCUCUUUCACAAAUAAAGUGUAGCAAAAUGGUAUUGAUAUUAACAUCACUUCAUUCCUGUGAAACGGGUUGUAUUGUCUCUGGUCUGUAUUGUUACUGUCUUAUCUCCAGAGGUAGAUUCAAGGUAAUAUUAGUCAAGACUAAGCUUCAGGACCUAUCACUUCCCUUGGGCUCAUUUCACGUGGAUCUAAAUUUUGACAUAUAAUCGUAUCUUUUUUCUUAAACAGGAACCCCAAAGUUGUAUAAGAUUCAGGCCCUAUAAAACCUGAUUCUACUCCUGCAGUUAUCUCUGACACCAAAGGUGCAUCGCAAGGUGAAAUAGUUGUCAACAGUAUUUUAAUAAGUCCUUGAAGCCACAUUCUAGUUUCUUAUUAUUAUCAUUUGGUAGACUCCUAAAAUUUGAUGUGAUUUUUGACCCAGAUGUUAAAAUGUAAAUUAUUCAAGGUGUAGUUUGCUCUCCAAAGGGAGUACGUAAAUGUGAUUAUAAAGUGAUUCUAAAAAUUCUGUAUUGCCAAUUCAGAUAUAAUUACUGGGUGAUUGAAGACUUUGUCUCCUCAUAAUAAUAAAUAAAUAUACCUGCUAUGCAUUGUAAAUAUUAAAUCAGAUUUUAUACAUCUUUCUACUAAACAACUUUAUUAGUUCACUAGGGCUGUCAUAAGAAAGUGCAGUAGAUACCCCUCUAUUAGCAAUUUUGCUUUCUGCAAUUUCAAUUACCUAUGGUCAGCUGCAGUCCAAAAAUAUUAAAUAGUAAAUUUCGGAAAUCAAGUUCUAAGUUUUAGAUUGCACAUCAUUCUGAGUAACAUGAUGAAAUUUCAUGCCAUCCUUCCCUGUCCCAUCUGGUACCUGAACCCUCUCUUUGUCCAGCAUAUCCACACUGGAGACACUCCCCACCCCUAAGUCGCUUAGUAGCCCUCUCCAUUAUCAGUUCCACUCUCAAGGUAUCACUGUGCUUGUGUUCAAGUAACAUUUAUUUUACUUAAUAAUGGCACAAAAGUAUAAAACUAGUGAUGCUGGCACUUCAGAUAUACCAAAGAGAAGCCAUAAAGUACUUCCUUUAAAGGUGAAAGUUUUUGACCUAAGAGAAGAAAUUUUUUUUUUUGCUAAAAUCUACAGUAAAAAGAAACCUUCUAUUAGUGAAAUUGUGAAGAAGGAAAAAGAAAUUUUUGCUAGUUUUGCUGUCGAACUUCAACUACAAAAGAUACAGCCACAGUGCCUGAUAAGCACUUGGUUAAGAUGGAAAAGGCAUUAAGUGUGUGAGUGGAAGACAUGACCAGAAAUGUCUUCUGAUUAAGAUCUACUGGGGGUCUUGGAAUGUAUUCCCCACAGAUAAGGGGGUACUACCAUACCACAUACUGGCGGGCUCAAACAGUAGAAAUUAAUUGUUUUACGGUUCUGGGGUCUGAAAGUUUGCGAUCUAAGUAAAGGCAGGGUGGGUUCCUUCUGAAGGCCAUGAGGGAGAAUAUGUUCCAGGCCUCUCUCCCAGCUUCUGGUGGUUUGCCUGCAACUUUUGUUGUUCCUUAGCAGCAGCAGCAGCCAAGGCAACAAAUCUCUGCCUUUAUUGUCACAAGGCAUUCUUUCUGUGUGCAUGUCUGUGUCCACAUUUCUUCUUUUUACAAAGACACCAGUCAUAUUGGAUUAGGGGCCCACCCUACUCCAGAAUGACCUCAUCUUAACACAACUAAUUCUAUCUGCAACGACCCUAUUUCCAAUUAGUUCACACUCUGAGGUCUUCAGGGUCAGGACUUCAACCUAUGAAUUUAGGGGGGCAGUAUAUACAAUUCAACCCAUAACAACAAUUCAUGAUAGUAAAUGGUUCAGAAAGAACACUGUCAACAUUCAUUAAUUGGUUUGCUUCUGCUGUAGACAGUGCUUAGCAUUCAAAAAAGCAGCUCUAGGUAUUUAUCUUCAGUAGUCACAGGCAGAUUUGGGACAGCUAAAAGUAUUGAGCAUUUGUUUAAUGUCAGUAGACAUGAAUAUAAGCGUUUAUUAUUUUUAUGGUCUGGAGUUUAGAAAAUAUCAUAUUUGCCCACUGGGUUGCAGCCUCAAGUCACAUUUCAAUUCUGGGGCCUGCAGCAGAAAACUUUUAAAAAGCAGCUGAUGUUGAAAGAUAUAAAUUAUGAUCCUUCUUGUCCUAUUACACCUUCACAGCUUCUUGGUUUUUCCUUUCAAGGGGGGAUACUGUGGACAGUUUUGGAAUUCUGUCGAAUAUUCAGGGUAUCUGUGUCUUAAUAAAACAUCCUGUAUUGAAUCUGUACUCACCCAUUAAAAACAAACUAUAGAUACUUCAUUAGAAAUAGAAUUUGAAAAUUCCAUCCUCUACACCUCUCACUGAGAUAAUGGCUUCCUUAAAUUUUUGAGCAAAGUUGAACAAUUCAUUUCAUCAUCUAUAAUUUAUUCUUAAUUUUAACUAAUGAAAUGGAAUCAUUAAGAAGGAAAUUAAGGGGGAGACAGCAAAGAAGAAAAAGAAGAAAGGGGGAUCACCAAAUGUGAAGAAAAGAGAAAAUACUUUUUUUCUGAAUUUUCAGAAAGCCUCUCUUAAAUAAGUAUUGAAGUUCCGUAAAUAAUUCUGUCUGCAGAGGAUAAAAGGAGCAGAUUGACCAAUUACUUUCAAAGUGUUUGAUCAUAUCCAUGUUUUCAUCAAUUAUUCAAGCUUUAGGAGUCAUCAAAGAAUCCUAAUGCGUAACUCAAAAUGAGGAGCAAAAGCUAAGAUAUUGGCAAAUGCUUUUCAUGUUUCAAAUUCCUCCCACUUAUAAGCAUAUGUGCUUUUGAAUGUUGGGCAGAUUUAAAUCUUUGUGCGUGGGAAGGAGGUUGACAAGUUAGCCUUUUGGACAAAAGGGAAGAAGGACAUAAAGAUGUUAAAAAGCCACGUUGGCAAGUAGAGCUGGAGGUACAGGAUGAAAUGACACCCUUGGGGUAAUGUGACCCAAUCUCAGGUUAUAUUCCAUUAUGCCACACCCUGUGCCUGGCUACACAUUUGCCACUCCAGGCCAUGCAGUGAUUCACCAUAUAGAAUAGUCAGACCUGAGUCUUUGAACAAAAACUAGCUGCCAAGAACAGUUUAAGAAUCAUAAGAAGAAUAAAAUUAGGUGAUUAGACAGAAGAAAGAGGAAGGAUGAUACAGUACGAUCCUAUAAUAAUGCAAAAGUAAGUUCCAAAGAAACGUUUCUACUAAGUCUGAAAUAUAUUACUUAGUUUUAUCCGGAUUGUAAGUUACCAGACCAUUUUAUGGGCGCUAUAAUGUCACUAGAAGUGCAUGUCUAACAAAAUAAUAGAGUACAUUACCAAUUCUGCUGUGAUGGCUACUGCAGAGAAACUAUUAGACCCAUUUGUCAAUGUACCUUGGUGUCUAACAAUUUUAAAGAAUGAGUAGUUGUGGAAACUGUUCAACAUUUUAAAGACAUCAUUUCUCCUCAGACACAUUCCAUUGAAUCAUCAAUUUUGGGUACAUCUAUUUGUCCACCCAUGCUUUUCCUGUAAAGCUGAUUGAAAAGAAAACAACAAAAACACAUUUUGAAUGGCAGAAUAGAAAAUACUAACGAUGUAUGAAUUUGAAAGGUCUAUUUAUUGUUUCAAACAAGAUUGAUAUUUUGUUAUAUUUUGGGUAUUGUGCAAGUUGGCACAAAACAUUAAAAUAGAAUAUAUACAAAGUAGAUCUUCAAAAUAUGAAAAUCUGCUUUGCAAUGAAAUAAAUUUGAGGUUGGAGAUAGCAGUAUUCGUGCCAUUAUAAAGAAUUUCUUUAGAGUGGAUACAUUUAGCAGGCAUUUUCAAAGCAUAGCUUUAGGAACAGUUUAUAGUAAUAGAUUAAUGCAAAGGAGUUUGCUUUACCUGCUCUCCCUUCAACCUUCAUUCACUGAUCUUGUGUUCCCAAUCCUUUAUAAUCCUAAACACCAACCCACUUCACCUUCCAACUAUUUUAACAAUUAUUAAAUGGGUGAGUUAAUAAGAGGAAAGAAGAGAGCAUGGCGAUUUAUUCCAAAAGAAAGAACUCCUUGUUUGCUCUGUGCCCUUGAGGAAGUCAGUUCCGUCAAUCAUUAGAUAGGGGGCUGGACUCGGUAAUCCAUGAAGUCCCUCCCAGAUCUACUGUGUUAAGAUGCUAAGUGAGGACACUAAAAUCAAGGCUUAUAAAAAAACAAAAGCAAAUGGCAGUGUGAAACCAACUUUCUUUUUUUUUUAGGGUUAUUAUAGUUUUUUUUUAAAUUAUACUUUAAGUUCUAGGGUACAUGUGCACAACGUGCAGGUUUGUUACAUAUGUAUACAUGUGCCAUGUUGGUGUGCUGCACCCAUUAACUCGUCAUUUACAUUAGGUAUAUCUCCUAAUGCUAUUCGUCCCUCCUCCCCCCACCCCAUGAUAGGCCCCGGUGUGUGAUGUUCCCCACCCUGUGUCCAAGUGUUCUAAUUUGUUCAAUUCCCACCUUUGAGUGAGAACAUGUGGUGUUUGGUUUUUUGUCCUUGUGAUAGUUUGCUGAGAAUGAUGGUUGUGUGAAACCAGCUUUCUAAAUUUUCUUCAAAUAUUUGAAAACAACUUUUCAGAUAUAAGCUUCAGCAUUGUAAUAUUUUGGAUUGUAUGCUACUUGGGAGGCUGGGGCAGGAGAAUGGUGUGAUCCCGGGAGGCGAAGCUUUCAGUGAUCCUAGGUCGCGCCACUGCACUCCAGCCUGGGCAACAGAGUGAGACUUCGGCUCAAAAAUAAAUAAAUAAGUAAAUAAAUAAAUAAUAAAUAAAUAAAAGAAAUGCUGUUUACUAGUUUUGGGACAUGGAGUAGAUCACUUCACCUUUAUAAACCAAAAUUCCCCACUGUGUAAAACAAGAAUAUUGAUAUUAGUGUAUAGGUAGUUGAAGAUUAAAUGAGGUGGUACAGGCAAAGGUUUAGUUCCAACAAAAUGUUCAGUAAUAUUAGCAUUUAUUAUUUUUAUCUAGAUGUGUAUUGGCAAUAAUUAAUGUAUUCAGUUACUAAUUCAAAAAUAUGCAUGUAUAUUUUAGAUCAAGCAUUGCAUUAAAUGCUAGGGACCCCACAGAACAAUCUCUUCUCCUCCCUGUUAGUUACUAUUUGAUUAUUUAAGAGUGAACUGAUAUAUGUUUGUGGGAGAGCAUAUAUUUUGAAUGUAUUAGCUUUUGUUUUAAAACUCUGUAUGACUGAGAUGGAAAUGUAACAAGAUUCAAGUGAGUAAAACAUAACUUUCAUAUUUCUGCUAGUAAGCACAAUUCAACUCUGGUCUUCCUUUUAUUGGUAGCAGAAAAUUCAGUCUUGCAAUUUGAGGUAACUUGGCUACCUCCUAUCUCAAAGUGAUCCUCUUUGGGUUCAAUUCAGGAUAUCCCACCACUGUAAUCACCCAAUGGGUUUUUCUUGCCUGCUGCACAGACAAAACCAGUUCACCGAGACCGUGGUAUUGUAAUAAAGAAAGAGUUUAAGUAAUGCGAUGCUAGCCACGUGGUAGAAUCACUUAAAUCAGUCAAAAGGCUCAGAGGGUUAGAGGCUUUCAAAUAGUUUUGUGGGCAGAAGACUACAGAAUAGGUGCUGCUUAUUAGCUGGGGAACCAAUUUUCCACAUCAUAGGGAUGUGGAAAAUGGCCCUCAUGCGCUGAGUCUGCCUCUGGCUGGGGCCACAGGAUGAUUGUGGAUUGUGUCUGGAUGGGGUCAGUCAGUUGCCGGAAUGUGAAAGUCUGUAAAACAUCUGGAAAGCGCAAUCUUGGGUUCUACAGUCAUGAUGUUAACUAUAGGAGCAGUUGAUGAAGCUAUAAAUCUUGUGACCCCUGGCUACAUGACUCUUGAGCAGUAAGGGAUUAUAGAAACCAUGCCUACAUUUUAGCAGACUUCAUGCCCCUCCCACCUAAUCUUGUAGCCUUCCAUUAGUCUUACAAAGGCAGUUUCAGCCCCCAGAGAGGGAUCAGUUUUAGGGAGGGACUAUUACCAUCUUUGCUUCAAAGUUAAAGGAUAAACUAAACUCCUCCCAUGCCUAGCCAGCCCCACACCCAGGAAUGAGCGAAGCCAGCAGCCUGCGAGGCUAGAAGCAAAAUGGAGUCAGCCAUGCUCAAUUUCUCCCACUGUCGUAACCUCUGCAAAGGAGGUUUCACAGCUAGGGCUGCCCACUCUGCAGCUUUGUGCAGCUGUGGACUCCCAUGACAUCAAGCUAGAGUGACUCUUUAGGCUUGCUGAUUGUCAACCCUUAACUCUGUUUUGUUCCUUAGCCAUGGUGUUGAGAACUUGUGAGUGCUAAAAAAACAAAAAACAAACAAACAAACGAAACCACCACAGGUGGGGCGGGGACUAUCUUAGGCCUUCUCUUUACCCAGAGCUGCCUUGCUGACAUUUCCACCUAUUGCAGCUUAGUUUGUUGAAGGCAAUCAGCAAGGUUAUUUUCUUCUCAAGUUUCAGAGUUCACUGGGAGUGAGUCCCCAGUACAAGAGUGACUAAAUAUUUUGGGAAGUUUCUAUCACCCAACUGGCCAGAGUUUCAACCCCAGAGCAGGUUCAGGGAAGACGGCAACCCAUACUGUCUACACUCCUUUUGUUUCACUUUCCCUAUCUCUCCUCUUCAGUGCUGUAGAAAAACUGCUCAUAUGGCAUCACUUAUCUUUUCCACCUUCACUGUGGCCUUGAACCCUUUGCUCCCAGUCCUAUAAGAUUUGGUUCUUGAUAUUUAAAUCCAAGCUUUUGGAACUUUUUUUCUCUCCAGCAGCUGGUACUUGCAAUUCAAAACCAUGGUUUUAAAGACGAUUGUCUGCACUGUUGACUUACAAGGGUCAAAUUAGUUGCUCAAAGGCCAAAAAUGUGCAUCUUUGUUCUCUCUGAAUCAACCUUACCCUGAGGCAUAAAGUCCUUUUUGCUGCUUAUAUAUGGUAAAAAAAACAUAACUAAAAUAAAUUGAAAAAUUCUUCACUUAGUUUAAUAUCAAAAUACCCCGCUACAGAACAAACCCACAGUGGAAUAAAAUGAUAGUUGUCCUGUAUAUUUAUCUAAGUUUGCCUGUAUAUUUAUCUAAGUUUAGCUUAUCUCCAUAAGCUAAAAUAAAAACAAAACAAUAAAUGUUUUAAUUAUAUACCUCUGUAGUCUAACUUAAAUAAUGUUCCUCCGUUAAAACAAAAUUAAUGCUAAAAUGUUUUUGCUAUAAUAGAGCUGCACAUGCUGUCACUAAAUUUGCUUUUCCAAAAUGUUUCAACACGGCCAUGCUGUCUUGGUACAAUCUUAGCUAUAAACAUGAUUCAUUUAUAUAUUGAAUGCCUAUGUGCCAGGCACUAGGUGUAAGCAACUGAGAAAGAAUGAUGGUCAUGUCCCUAAUUUCCUAAAUGCUGAGAAUUCCUCUCUGACCAAAUGAACAUCAUUUUUCAAACAGUAACAGCCUCCCAAAGCUUGCCUUUCCAGGAAGUUCACAGCCAAACCUGGAAUCUUCACCUGUUCUGUAUGGUGGUAGAGUUAAUUGUGUAUUUUGUAUUUCUUUCUCCACCACUGGAGAGAGCACUCUGUUACAUGCCCAAAAGAGUUAUUUCAGGAUGCACAAUUUUAAGGCAGAGUUAAAAAGUUAAAGGCAGAGUUUAAAAUCCUUUUUUUGAAGGCAGAGAUUAAAAGUCUCUUUUAAGUGAAUAGUAUACAGAAAAACAAUGUAUUUCUUUUUUUUUAGAAAACAAUUAAAACAUAUUUCCAACCUAACAGCUGUUAUUUUCCCAAGAUACAGUUAGCUGUAGAAGGGUAGGAAAUGAUUCUGUAAGUUUAAACAGCACAAAUUUUGUGUCGUUCCUUUCCUCCUGCCUUCUUGCUUUCAAAUGGAUGCAGCAUAAAGACAUCUCUCCUCACAGUUCUUGGUUAAUAAAAUAAUCUCAUAGUCUGACUCUAAUAUUACUAAACUCAAAUGAAUAAUAUAUCAAAAUCUGAAGAGAUGAAUCAUAUUUUUUGGCUACACGGGGGCUUUCAAAUCUCCAUUAUGUCUAGGUUUUUAAAACAAAAACAUUUAUUUUGAGCUUUCUUUAUUCUUAUAGUACAUGAUCUGAUGGGAAGUAAGUAUGAAUUAAAGAUGAUCAUGAGAUUAAAAUAAAUUAACUCUUUCAGGACACCAGAGUUUUAUAACUUAGACACUACAUUUUCACAAAUGCGAAAUUUGAAAUAUACAUUGUUCACCUCCUCCAGGCCAUUGUUUCUCAAACUUCUACAAUAUAUACCGUGUCUUUAAGACAAAAACAAAAACUAGUACAAAAAUCUUCUCUUCGAACCCCAGUGUUAAAUCAUUUUUAUUACAUUGUUACUUAAAAAUAUGCAAACAAAACCAAGCAUAAACCUGACCAACACAGUGAAACCCUGACUCUACUAAAAAUAAAAAAAUUAGCCGGGCAUGGUGGCAGGUGCCUGUAAUCCCAACUGCUAGGGAGGCUGAGGCAGGAGAAUCACUUGAACCCAGGAGGCAGAGGUUGCAGUGAGCUGAGAUGGCGCCACUGCACUCCAGCCUGGGCAACAGAGCCAGACCCUGUCUCAAAAAAGAAAGCCAAGCAUAAACACUCUGUGCUUAUAUCUCUCACAAAACAUAAUUAUAACGCAGUGUGCUGUAUUAUGAUAAUUCUAAUAUUUUUUGGAGCCUCUGCACAGUAUCGUUGUUUGCCUUUUGCUAUCUCUGUUCUUUUCUCAUUAAAAUUUCUUGAGGCCAGUGGCCAGGCGGGGUGGCUCACUCCUGUAAUCCCAGCACUUUGGGAGGUGGAGGCAGGCAGAUCACCUGAGGAUGGGAGUUCGAGACCAGCCUGACCAACAUGGAGAAACCCCCUCUCUACUAAAAAUACAAAAUUAGCUGGGCGUGGUGACGCAUGCCUGUAAUCCCAGCUACUCGGAAGGCUGAGGCAGGAGAAUCACUUGAACCUGGGAGAUGGAGGUUGUGGUGAGCUGAGAUCGCGCCAUUGCACUCCAGCCUGGGCAACGAGAGCAAAACUCCAUCUCAAAACAACAACAACAAAAACAACAAAAACUUCUUGAGGCCAAAACAAUAGUAUCUACAAACAUAAACACUGGGUUCAUAUGGCAGUACUUGGCUAAAUUAUUAUGGGAAAUCAAAACACAAAUAAGAAUAUUCAAAGAUAAUUUUCCAAAGGGACAAAUUCAAAUAUAAAAAACUAUCAAAAUGUUAUUUAACUCAGUUAUUAACAAGGAAACCAGUAAAAUGUUAACUGGUUUAAUAUAGAAUUCAAAUUAAUACACAUAUAUGGUUGAGUCAGGAAUGUUGAAAUGAAUCUACAAAUAGAUGAAAAACUGGCUUUUUCCCCUAGGUUGCAGUGGAGAGAAAGAUCAGUUGUUCCUCCACCAAAAGGAAUUUACAUGUCUUUGGAUAAGUAUUAUUUUAAUUGCUACCAUUUAUAUAUAAUUUAUAGCCUUGUAAAAUAGCUCAAUCAGCCCUCCAUAGAAUCAGAUAACUUGAAACUAUAUGUUAAAUAUAUGUUAAAUAAUGCCUGCUUUUCCAAUGAAGAUACCUGGUGUUCUUUUGGUUCAUUAUUUGGCUCAUAAUUUGUUCAUUCAGUAUAUUUAAGAGGAAUGUACAGACCCUAUAGAACCUAUCCAUGGAUCGCAUGGAAAUUCCAAAACCCUCUGUCUCUAUUGCACACAACAAGCAUCUUCAAUGGAGCUAUCUCCGUUAAGAACUGACCUCUAGCCACAUAUAGAAGCUCCAUAUGAGCCCUAUUGUCUUUAAGGAAUAUAUGGCUCUUACUUCAGAUAUAAACAUAAGCAACCUCUUUUAAUAAGUUGGAUGACCUCUUCUGAGGGAAUAACUAUGACAACUAAUCUCACAUCUUUAUAUGUGAAAAUUUUCGCCUAAGGAUAGAUAAUUACAAUGAUAAGCCAAGCCUUCAGUAAAAAUGUAUUGAGUUUUGUUCUUUCUUUUUUUGGGAGGGAGUGGAGUGGAGAGCAAUUACUAUACCAGGUACUGUACUAAGUACUUUAUGUCAACAAAAAAAAAGUCAAACUCUAUAAAGUAUUUAAAAAGGUUUAUUUUGAGCCAAAUACGAGUGGCUAAGGCCCAAGACAGUCUCAAGAAGUACUGAGAACGUGUGCCCAAGGUGGUUGGAUUACAACUUGAUUUUACACAUUCUAGUGGGACAGAACUUACAGGCAGGCGUCAAUCAAUACUAUGAGUUAUACAUUGUUUGAAUCCAUAAAAGUGGGACAACUAGAAGCAGGGUCUUCUAGGUCGUAGGUGGAUUUGAAGAUUUUCUGAUUGGCAAUUUGUUGAAAGAGUUAAGUUAUUAUCUGAAGACCUGGAAUCAAUAGAAAGGAGUGUCUAGGUUAAGAAGAGAUUGUGGAGACCAAGGUUCUAUUAUGUAGAUGAAGUCUCAUAAGUGGCUACCCUUAGAGGCAAUAGGUGGCAAAUGUUUCCUAUUCAGAUCUUUAAAAGGUGCUUAACUCUCAGCUAAUCUCUUCAGGCUCAGAAAAAGAACUAGAAAGGGAAGGGGAUUCUCUACAGAAUGUACACUUCCCUCACAAGAGACAACUUUGCCGUGGCCAUUUCAAAAUAUGUCCAAGAAAUAUAUUUCAGGGUAAAAUAAUUUCUUUCAGGGCCUGCAGUCUGUCAUGUGAUGCUAGACUAGAGUGAGUUAGAAUUCGGUAUCUUACAGCUGUAAAGAUACUUUUACAUUUUGUCAUUCUUAAGAUCUCUGUUUCAGUGCUAAUGCUGGUCAGUUGUGCCUGAAUUCCAAAGGGAAGAGAGUAUAGUAAGGCAUGUCCAACCCCCACUUCCCAUCAUGGCCUGAACAAGUUUUUCAGGUUUACUUUGGAAUCCUCUUGGCCAAGAGGAGGGAUCCAUUCAGUUAGAUGGAGGGCUUAGAAAUUUAUUUUUGGUUUACAUGCAUAUAUAUUUUUUCAUUAAAUAUCAAAAUAUAAUGCUAUUAAUGUGUACAUUUUAUGGGUGAGAAAAUUCUGCCUGAACCACCCACAUGGCAAGUUUUGAAAAAAAGAUUAUUUGAAUGAAAAACAGGACAAAACCAAGUGUGUCCUGUUUGUGUAAGCAUUUGAUGAGGUCUUCUGUAACUAACAAUCAGGAUAGUAUCUUAAUUAGAUUAGAUGGAACAACUGGUUUGCUAUCCCAAAGUCAGAUGUUCAGUCAAUAUUUAUGGAACGUGUCCUAGUCAUUCUCACUUCAUCUGGGAAAUUGAGUGUCCAGGCUACAUAUUUCAUAGUGCUAUGUAUACAGUUGUCAUAGCACUUGACAAAUGGCAUUAAGUUAUCUUGUAUGUGUUUAUGUCUCCUUUGACUUCAAUGGCUAAGCUACGAAGUUAAUUUAGAGGAAUGGCCGUGUGUCCUUAGUACUUUGCAUGAAGACUGCCACAUCCUAGGAGCUAAAUAUAUGCUUUUGAAUUAAUCUAAACUAUGCAUAUGCAUUAAAGAUAAGCCGUAAAUUUGAACCUCUGGAAAAAUUUACUCCCAAGUCACUAGUUCCAAAGAUUUCACUUCUGUUUUCAAAAUGUUCAGUGCCAUUAGUUAGAUUUUAGUGUCAAUAGAUGCAUUAAGUUAUAGCUGCUUAAAAUUUACUCUCAGGACACAGAGGAAAGGCUUGUCUUAGCAUUAGAUACAAGCCCUGCAGACUGAAGGUCGUGAUAUCUUUGGGCGUUACUGGAGAAGAAAGCCAUGGCCAUGAAAAACCAUUAGAAAUUAUCUAGAAUUCUGUACCACAAUUAUGUAUCUAAUGGAUUGAAAUUUGAGAAAGUCUUAAGUGCAAAUAUUUAUGAGAUUCUUCAGGCUGGACGUGGUGGCUCACACCUGUAAUCUCAGCACUUUGGAGGCCAAGGCAGGUGGAUCACAAGGUCAAGAGAUCAAGACCAUCCUGGCCAACAUGGUGAAACCCCAACUCUACUAAAAAUACAAAAAUUAGCUGGGUGUGGUGGCGCAUGCCUGUAGUCCCAGCUACUCAGGAGGCUGAGGCAGGAGAAUUGCUGGAACCCAGGAGGCAGAAGUUGCAGUUAGCCGAGAUCGUGCCACUGCACUCCAGCCUUGUGACAGAGUGAGACUCUGUCUCAAAAAAAAAAAAAAGAAAAGAAAAGAAAAGAUGCUUUAUAUCUCACAAACUAAAUACCACAUUUCCUUUAAAGUACCGUAUUUAGGCCGGGCACAGUGGCUCAUGCCUGCCCAGCGCUUUGGGAGGCUGAGGCAGGCAGAUCACUAGGUCAAGAGAUCGAGACCAUCCUGGCCAACAUGGUGAAACCACGUCUCUACUAAAAAUACAAAAACUAGCUGGGUGUUGUGGCGCACGCCUGUAGUCCCAGCUACUCAGGAGGCUGAGGCAGGAGAAUCACUUGAAGCCGGGAGGCGAAGGUUGCAGUGAGCCGAGAUCACACCACUGCACUCCAGCCUGGUGAAAGAGUGAGAACAAAUUAAAAAAAUUUAAAACAAGUACCAUAUUUAUGAGAAAGUAAAUAUGAAAGAAUGACGAGGAAAUACAGAGAACUGAUACUCACACUGGCCAAAAGAAAGAAUAGAAAGCAAAAAUAUUGAAGUGGGAUUGGGAGAGUAGAAAUUGGAGAAGAAGGAAAAAUCACACAAGAAUGUUGGGAAAAUGUUCUGUUAUGUUAACUCCUUUAAUUAUCAACCAUUUGGCUGUAGAAUAAAAAAUAAAACAUGAGAUUUAAAAAUGUUUAUAUUUUUGUUAAAAUAUGUACUUUAAAAAAAUAUUAAAUAUGUGAAAUGUAUACAAACAGGAACUAUAAUUCCUCAUCAGUAAUAAAAGAUUUCUUUUGAAUUUAUCACUAACCAGAGUGAGAAAGUAAAGAAACUGUCCUUGUAGAGUUAGGAUUCAAAUCUGACCAUGUUUUCUGAGGGUGUAAAGUGGCUCAUCUAUUUGAAUUAGUUGUUUCAAGUCCCACUUACUUUGUUCAGAAGGCCACUUUUUGUCCUGCCAGUAGACUGUAGCCCAAACCCUAAAUUGUCUGGUCAGAGACUGGGAAGGUAAUGUUGUGCGUGUUUUGCUGAUUAAAUAUAAAACAUUCAACAUCCUUUAUGGCCUCUGUUUAAAGUAAGCUUCUCAUUCCAAAGCGUAUUUUUGAACUACCCACUGUUAUUGGCAUGUUUCCUCUUAGAGUAUUCUUUAACAGAUAUUGGUUUCCUUCUAGACAGUUUCACAAAAUAACAAUAGGUUAGCCUUCCUUAGAAGGCUUAAAAAUCCAAUAACUCUUUAUAUGGUUCAUAUUUUAUUUAUUUUUCUCAUGUUAAUAGUAUUCUUUUAUCUGUUUAAUCUUAUGACUCCUCUCAUUUUGGAGAGAUUUUGAACAAAUUGGUUGGGAAACCAAAAAAGAAACAAGAGGAUUUUUUAAUACUAGUUAGGCUAUAAAAUAUUUUCAUAUGCUUUAAAAAUGGGAUUGCCCACAGAAGGACUUCAUUUUAAAGUGUGAGUUUGGUAGUAGUGAGGGGGAUAUAUGUAUCUGAAAGCAUUUUAUAUUGGAAAACGGGUCUAUUUGUGGUUAUACUUUGUUUGUAUAUCAAAUACUGCACCUGUCACAAGCUUGGAUUUAUCGUGAGUAUGCAUAAUGCUUGCUUUUGGGAAAGCCUGCAAAUCCCCCAUUGGCAGCAGAAUGACCAGAAGUAGAUGCACCUGUCUUCCCAGCUGGGACUUGCUCAUGGAAAAGAAGGUCAUUUAACACCAUGUUAUUCCUGUGGACAGCUGUAUAUGUAAAAUGCCUUAGGACAUAGACGACCUAAAUUCUGUUAAAAAAAAGGUCUUCAAUGGCCAAAUGAAAUUUGACUUUGAAAAGUAUUUUAAUGUUUUGAUUCAUUAGAUUUGGAGCAUAUAUAGGGUUGGUUUAAUAGAAAAACAUUAUUUGUUUUGCUUUGGUCUAAGCACUCUAUCAGCUUUUAAUGACUCAGCAAACACCAAUAUUUUCAGCACACAUUGGCUUAGGGUUUAGUAUAAAGUAGUUCAUUCUGUUUUGAUGCAACUCUUGGUUAAAAUAUAGGCCUUCUCCCAAUGCUACAGUGAUAAUUCUUUGUUUUUGUCUACUUUAAUUGUCUGUUUUCCCCCAACAGACUCUAAUGUCUGUGAGAAUAAGGGCUGUGUCUAUUUUGCUAACCAUUAUUUUUUCUAGCACACUGCCAUUGUAUUAAUUCUGGGUAUAUGUGUGCUUAGUAAAUCUUUCUCAAGUGGAUAAAUGAAUGAAGGAAUAAAGAACUGGUUUUCACUGUACAGUUCAUCUUAAAGACUGUCACUCAAAAUCAUACCAAAACUUGAGAAGCCUCGGUCCUAUUGUUUGUCUGUUUGUUUUUUAAUGUAAGUACAAGUUGAGUUACAAUAAAGUAUACAGAUUUUAAGGUCACAGUUCCAUGAAUUUUGUCAAGUAUAUACACCCAUGUAACCAUUAUCCAAUCAAGAUAGAGAAUUUUUUCAUUAUUCCAGAAAGUUCCCUCUUGCUACAUUUCUGUCAAUUCCUCACAGCCACUGUUCUGAUGAUCAUUAUAGCUUAUUUUUGCCUUUUCUAGAACUUCAUAUAAAUGUAACUAUAUAGUAUGCACUUUUUUGUGUCAGGCUUGUUUCAUGCAACUUUAAGAUUUUUCGAUUUAUCCAUAGAUGUUUAAUUGAAUUCUUGGGAAUCAAGAACUUAGCCAUGUUAAAAAUAAGAUUAAUAAUGAAGGACUAUGAUAUUACAAAAAAAAAAAAAUACUUUGUGUCUCCUUGGAGGAUUUAUUGAUGACAUUUUCCCCAAUCUACAACUAUGUGCUUUUAAGAAUUCUAAAAAUAUACAGAAUGAUUGUUAGAAGUAGAGUUCAGAGGUGCCAUCAAACUAACGUCAUUGUACUAUGAACUUCCAUAGGCAGAUCAUUUGAUAAGCCAAGCAGAUCAAGAGGGGCACAUUUUAGAGCAGGUAACUCAGCCUGGGCUUUCUGACUUCUCCAGUGUUAUACAUCACUACACCAUUGGCGUCCUUUUUCCAGAACACACUUCUGUAGAUAAUGACCUAUGCAUAACAGUUUGUAAAGGUUAAGGAAAGGCUCCAAAAUCAGGUAUUCCACUGAAAGUCUUCUUUAAAAUAGAUUUUUCAGUAACAGAUAACUGGGGUGUAGAGGUGUUUGGGUUGAAUUGCAACAAGGUUUACAAAGAAACAGUCAGUUUGCAGGCAGUGGAAAGAAGCUUGCCAAGUAAAGCCUGUAGAAAAUGGCUUCAUUGAAUUAGAACAGUCUGUGAUCAACUGCCAAAGCCAGCUUAUUUUCCUUGCGAGUUCCAGAAAAGAAUGCCUGAGACUUUGUGUUGUUGGAAGGCUAUCUUAUAGAACAUGCUGGCAGAACACACUUUUUCACUGGCUCACGUCAGUAUUAUUAUAGACUUGAUGGGGUACUUUGGGAUUUGGUAGGGAUUUUUACAUUAGAAAAACUUAGGCAUAGGAGAUUAGGAACCAAAUGUGUUAGUUUAUCAUAGCAGAGUAAAGCAACAAGACAGUAUUAAGGAAGCCACAGACAAGACUGUUUAGAACUAACAAUAUUCUACUUCUCUUGUGGAAAUACUUGCUAUUAUAAGUGAGACCGCAGAAUAAAAUUAAUGUCUGGGGAAAGUAAGCAAAUAAUUGUGGAAAAUUGUUAAAAUGACUUUAUAACCAGUAAAGACAUCAUUUAUUCAAAGACAGAUGUCUUUGAAUAAACGGAUAAGGAGGAGAUUAUAAUGAUAUAAAGGGAGAAAAUUCCUUUUCAAAUUAAGUGUUCCUCAAGUGCUGAUUGUUUUGUGCAGAAUAAUUUGAUGUAAGAUAUGUGGAAAUUUUAUGAACUGGUAAAAAGAGAAUCUGAACAACUUGAAACAAAGUGCUAAUGUCAGCUGAAGUGCCUCCAAAGUUACUCAUAUAUUUUUCUUUCCUUUUAGACCCAUUAGAAACGCUUCAAGAGCUGCUCAGUCCAGGAGUGGAGGGAUUUUGUGAAGACACAGAUGCUCCCUAAAAGGAGUGCAGAAAUUUUCAUCAUAGGUUCUCUUGCUGUGCUGCUGGGUCCUCAGAAGUGUUCUGGAGAUCGCCUCUUUGAAAGCGGCUACGCAGCUUGCUCCUGGCACGGGCACCUUGAAUCUCCUCCUCACACAGAUGGAGACCAUGCUUGAUUUCCUGAACUUGUAGUAAGAAGAAGGAAAACACAGCACGCUGGAGCCAACAGAGUUAAGAGGAAGAUUUAUGAGUCAUGGAACCCUCCAUCAGAUUUGGAAGAAAGUAGAAUGAGCGCAGAGGUGACAGACAGCCACUGAGGCCCAUGGACAAUCUCCACCUCACGCUUCUCUAUCAAACUUGAAGAUUUAUUAGUAAUAUGCUGCCUUUGGAAGAUGAAAACAAACUAGUGCCAAGGAGGCGUAUUCUUCAAUAUUUGGAAUAGACGUGUUCUCAAGACAAUGGCUUCAAAGGUCUCCUGUUUGUAUGUUUUGACAGUUGUGUGCUGGGCCAGCGCUCUCUGGUACUUGAGUAUAACUCGCCCUACUUCUUCUUACACUGGCUCCAAACCAUUCAGCCACCUAACAGUUGCCAGGAAAAACUUCACCUUUGGCAACAUAAGAACUCGACCUAUCAACCCACAUUCUUUUGAAUUUCUUAUCAACGAGCCCAAUAAAUGUGAGAAAAACAUUCCUUUUCUUGUUAUCCUCAUCAGCACCACUCACAAGGAAUUUGAUGCCCGUCAGGCAAUCAGAGAGACGUGGGGGGAUGAGAACAACUUUAAGGGGAUCAAGAUAGCCACCCUGUUCCUCCUGGGCAAGAAUGCUGAUCCUGUUCUCAAUCAGAUGGUGGAGCAAGAGAGCCAAAUCUUCCAUGAUAUCAUCGUGGAGGACUUUAUUGACUCCUACCAUAACCUUACCCUCAAAACAUUAAUGGGGAUGAGAUGGGUGGCCACUUUUUGUUCAAAAGCCAAGUAUGUCAUGAAAACAGACAGCGACAUUUUUGUAAACAUGGACAAUCUUAUUUAUAAAUUACUGAAACCCUCCACCAAGCCACGAAGAAGGUAUUUUACUGGCUAUGUCAUUAAUGGAGGACCGAUUCGGGAUGUCCGCAGUAAGUGGUAUAUGCCCAGGGAUUUGUACCCAGACAGUAACUACCCACCUUUCUGUUCGGGGACUGGCUACAUCUUUUCAGCCGAUGUAGCUGAACUCAUUUACAAGACCUCACUCCACACAAGGCUGCUUCACCUUGAAGACGUAUAUGUGGGACUGUGUCUUCGAAAGCUGGGCAUACAUCCUUUCCAGAACAGUGGCUUCAAUCACUGGAAAAUGGCCUACAGUUUGUGUAGGUAUCGCCGAGUUAUCACUGUGCAUCAGAUCUCUCCAGAAGAAAUGCACAGAAUCUGGAAUGACAUGUCAAGCAAGAAACAUCUCAGAUGUUAGGAUUUUUACCAAUGUAAAUAUGUUUCUUUUCUUUUUUUAAGAAAUGGGACCUAAGGUGUUGGUAUUUUCCAGGUGUCGGGGGAAAUGAACUGGUGAAGGGGUUUUGUAAAGUUUUUGCUUCCUGCUAUAAGUUCUUUUCUUGGAUUACCAAUUUAUGAAUGUUAGACUCUGGUCAUAGAAACAAUAAAUGAGUUAGAAGGGCCAGAUUUCAUUCUCAGUCCCAGAGCAUUGCUAUUUAUCUCAAAAAGUGACUUCCAAACAACUCUUAGGAUUGACGUACCGUGCAUCUGAGAUAAAAAUUUGGUUCUGGGAAACUGAAACUCACAGUAAUGUGUCAUAUCAUCCCUGCAAAAAUUAAUACACAAAUAGAAACCAUUUUCAAAAGCAAUUCAGAAAGGAUGCACAGUCAGGAAGACACACUGGAUGUGAUUAUUAAUAUCGUGUGUGUUGUUACAUUAUAUUUUUACAUAUAUUCCCAUGUAAUGUGUACAGUCUUUGCAGUUCCACCAAGAAAUGAACUUGGUACCUGCAGAGUGGCUGCAGUUAAAUAGAUGGGAGUUUAAAUUUGAGAAUCAAACAUUCUAUGUGUUUGGAAGACAACUCUGCUUGCUCAUCCAAGGAUUAAAUCUGGUCAGCAGGUGGAAUGUGUAUAAAAUGCUACUUAACAAAGUAAACAAAAGAUUUUUUUUUUCUUUUUUUUUCUUUCUUUUUUGUUUUGCUCUUUCAGAACAAACAUUAAAUGGUGCCUCCAAGGAAACUUUGCCAAAUAUAAUCUCACCUGCUUCCUUCCAGACAGUGUCGCUAAGUGCAUUUCACAGUUUUUGGAUCUGGCAGGCAUAUGUCUCUAUGUAGAAAAUAAGUUGGUUGGAGGCCAGAGAACAAUAAAUCACAUUGAGAAAAUACAAAUUUAAGUAUGCAUUAUAAUUAACAUAAGCUUAGCAAUAGUAUAAGAUGCCCCCACACACAGACAUUUGCAAAGCACAUGAGAAAAUCUUUAAGGGUGUCAAUAUUAUUGAAAGACUUGGCCCUACUUGCUAACAUCUGAAAACACCAGAGCAUGUUCAGCAGCAAUGCUGUUAUGAGGUAUUCUGGGGGCUCUGUGAUUGAGGAAGGAUGGGGAAGGCCAGGUUCGGGUCCCGUUGAUGCCACCAUACUUAUUGGGCCAUAUGAGUAGGCAUCGUAAUCUUGUGCUUCAAUGUGUUCAUUUAUAAAAAUGGCUGUAAAAAACACCUACCUCACAGGUGCUGUGAGAGCAAAUUGCAUUUGCUAAGUAUUUUGAGAUCCUUAGCUUAAAAGGUGCUACGUAAUGCAAUGUAUCAUGUAUUAUGCUAAAUGCUAAAAUAAUUGCAUAAUUACAAUGAUGGUCAUCAGUAGCAGUAAUAUCAUCUUAAUAUAAAAUCUGCUGAAAUAAAGAUCAGCUGUGAACUAUCACUGCACCUAAUUCUACCAAGGCUUGACUUUUCCUUGGCUGUAAUUUAGGUGUUUGGGAAGGCUUCCAUUUCUCUGAGAUUUCUUCUGGUUUCAAUGAAUAAGUGACUAGGUCAGUGUGUUGCCUUGAUAUCCCAAGGUGCUGAAAGUAGAGGCAGCUGCCUUUCUUUGGGAAGGAACCUCUGGUUGGGGUAUAUUACAGUAAAUGAAGCAUAUACUUUGCAAAAUGCAUCACGACAACUUAGAUCUCAGGAACCACUGAAUCUGAAUUCUCUCUAAGAAAUUUGAGCGCAGGUAAAGCUAGUUCACCUCUUUCAGAAGCAGCAGAAUAGGCAGUCAGCAAACCUGCACAUUGCACAUCUUCUACCAUUUAUUAGAAAACACCUGUUUGUUCUCAAAGAAAGCCCCACAGCUGAAAGAGUGUACCUUUUUUAUUUAUUUACUUUUUUUUUUUUUUUUUUUUUUUUUUUUGAGACGGAGUCUAGCUCUGUGGCCCAGGCGGGAGUGCAGUGGCACAAUCUCGGCUCACUGCAAGCUCCGCCUCCCGGGUUCACGCCAUUCUCCUGCCUCAGCCUCCCGAGUAGCUGGGACUACAGGCGCCCGCCAUCACGCCCGGCUAAUUUUUUUGUAUUUUUAGUAGAGACGGGGUUUCACCGUGUUAGCCAGGAUGGUCUCGAUCUCCUGACCUCGUGAUCCGCCCGCCUCGGCCUCCCAAAGUGCUGGGAUUACAAGCGUGAGCCACCGCGCCCGGCCCUAUUUACUUAUUUUUUAACCUGACCCCUGGAGCCCCCCGUAGGAGUUGAUAGCAAACAGAUAGACACAAUGAAUAAGUGGAAGUCAUGGCUUGUUUCUGCAAAACACGAUCUCUCAUCCCCCACCCGAAAGGACCUGAUAUGAGACAAGACUUCCCAUCCCUUAACACAUCUUCAUCUUAUGGUCAGCAGGACUGCUGGUUUUGAUUAGACAAUAGCAAUUAGGUAACCUGGGGAGAGAUGGAUCAGCACAAGGUGAACCACCCUCCAACCUGCAGCCUCAACUGCUGUGAGUUCCAAUCACUGGGAAAGUCUCACGACUUCUUACUUGGUUUACCUUCGAGUUGUGCAGCUGAAUCAAGCCUCUGUCUCAUACUAUUGCCUUGCAUCUACCCCAUGCUCAGUCAAACCACCUCUGGUGUCAAGAAAUUACACAUUAUAAACAUCAUAUAUGUACACCUAUGAAUCGUUUUAUAUGUGUGUGCAUACAUUAUGAUACAGCCCUGAUCUUUAAAAGGAGCAAAAAUCAGAGAAUCGUAUGUCUUAAAGAACUAUUUCCUUACUUUUUUAUGCUAGGUAAUGCCCAUGUGACAAACAUGUAAAUAUUCAUCAAAGACCACAUGUAUAUAUUUUAAAGGCAUUUUUUCUUCUCCCCAACUGUAUGUAUAGCUAGAAUCUGCUUGCUGUGUAACCUUUUCUUCUGCAUGGAGCUUUUGGUGAAGCAAGGCCAUUUGUCCAGUGUUUCAUAGCCUUAAGCAUGUUUGCCCUUCGUUUUUUGAAUGUUCAAAAAAUGUUUAAGUGAUCAAGAAAAAGCUCUAACUUUCGACUUUUGUUAAUUUUAUGACAUGACACUGGCCAAAAUAUUGUUUCAAUUACUGUUGAGCCAUUCUUAUCAUUUCCCUGACAUAAAAUAUGCAAUGUUUUAGACAGUAUUCUACCAAGAGUCUCUCAGACAAUUUUUACAAAAACUCUUUUUUUCCAUUAUGCACUGGAUAAUAACAGUAUCAGUGUCUAUGUUCUUAAAGUUCCUUUUUUUAAUUUACUUUUUGGAAAAACGUUUCUCUUUGGUGGCUAGUUUCGGUGGCUUGGUGUCUUCUUAUAUUGGAACAAGUGUCCAUUUCAAUAUGUAAUAUUGUAUUUUUAAAUAACCAGAAUCAACAAAGCGAAGAUCACUUUUAAUUUGGAUUCAAUUCAGAAGAAUAAAACCCCUUUGCGUGACACGAUAUGGGGAAAAUAAACUAUUUACAGAGGAGCCAAGGAAGAAGUUUUUCGAUCAAAUCUCUUCUAUCAAAAGACAAUGGAAUAUUUACCUAAAGCAUCUGGGAUUCAUUUUUUACCUUUCCUAAUAUGUGGGUUUAGUGGGAGAAUUGAUUAUGUCAUUUCUUCUGUAAAGGUGAAAAUCGUUUUUAUAAACAACAAAGUAACUUGUGAAUGAAAGAAGUAAUUUACUAGAACAACGCUUGUUGAUGAUAAUUGACAUUUAGGUAUAACGUCAUAUAUGAAUGAUUGUAUUUAUGUAUUUAUUUGUCAAAAUUGUACAUACUGUUUCGCCAAAAGUAAUUGUCUGUAAAAGUGCACUCUCCAGGUUUGUAGUACUAUUUAGGGUUACAUGGGUUGCCAAUCAAGCUGCUAAUCAGAAUACUAUUUUUUUGUAUCAAUGUUAUAAAACUAAAAAUGACAGACACUGAAGAUAUCAUUACACUUUCUUCACCUUCCUCUUGAAAUGUAAACUGUUGACUGAAAGCGCAAUGCUUAUGUACAGGCCCAUCUGUCAUGAGGAAGAUUAUGGUUCCAUAAAGCUGAUUUUUUUAAACCAUUGGGACAAAUAAACAGAAGGAGAACAAA